GAUCUGCCCACCUCCGCCUCCUAAAGUACUGGGAUUACAGGUGUGAGCCACUGCACCUGGUGGAAUCCUUGGAAUUUUCAAAGUGACACAGCUACUGAGUGCAAUGCCGCCUCCACAGAAAAUCCCAAGCGUCAGACCCUUCAAGCAGAGGAAAAGCUUGGCAAUCAGACAAGAGGAAGUUGCUGGAAUCCGGGCAAAGUUCCCCAACAAAAUCCCGGUGGUAGUGGAGCGCUACCCCAGGGAGACGUUCCUGCCCCCGCUGGACAAAACCAAGUUCCUGGUCCCGCAGGAGCUGACCAUGACCCAGUUCCUCAGCAUCAUCCGGAGCCGCAUGGUCCUGAGAGCCACGGAAGCCUUUUACUUGCUGGUGAACAACAAGAGCCUGGUCAGCAUGAGCGCAACCAUGGCAGAGAUCUACAGAGACUACAAGGAUGAGGAUGGCUUCGUGUACAUGACCUACGCCUCCCAGGAGACAUUUGGCUGCCUGGAGUCAGCAGCCCCCAGGGAUGGGAGCAGCCUUGAGGACAGACCCUGCAAUCCUCUCUAGCCCAUGUCGGGAAGGAUGUGUGCUCUGACAGACGUGUCAGAUGCUGGCAGAAGGGAUUGGUUUUCUCCUGUGUAUACAGUGGAGGAGUCUGAGAAGCAGGGAUGCCUGGGGUGAUCAGCUCCAACCAGUGGCAGCAGAGUGGUGGCUCUUCCUAGUUUAGUUUUUGUGCUCCGUGUUCUUGUGUCCUUCUAAGAAAAAUGUGGGCUGCUCUUGAAAGUUAUAUAAUUAUCAUUUUUUUUUUUUUGAAACAGGGUCUUGCUCUAUUGCCUAGGCUGGAGCACAGUGGCAUGAUCUUGGCUCACUGCAACCUCCGCCUCCUGGGUUCAAGUGAUUCUUCUGCCUCCACCCCCCGAGUGGCUGGUAUUACAAGCACAUGCCACCACACCAGGCUAAUUUUUGUAUUUUUAGUAGAGACGGGGUUUCACCAUGUUGGCCAGGCUGGUCUCGAACUCCUGACCUCAGGUGAUCCACCCACCUCGGCCUCCCAAAGUGCUGGGAUUACAGGCGUGAGCCACUGCAUCCAGCCAUAUAACCGUAUUCUAAAUAAGAAAUGGUUGGCUUGUGUGAUGGUUUUGUGUAAUGAGCUAGAGAUAAUAUUUUAAGUGUCUUCUGUGGUAUAUGUGGGAGGGCCAUUAAGGAGUGGGUUUCACUCCCUGCAUGUGGGCAGGUGUCC